AAAGCGGACCCGCGGACGGUGGCGUUAAGGGAACGCUGAGGUCCCGCGCUCCCCGACCGAGGUAUAUCUCCAUGAAUAACCUAAAUGAUCCCCCAAAUUGGAAUAUCCGGCCUAAUUCCAGGGCGGAUGGUGGUGAUGGAAGCAGGUGGAAUUAUGCCCUGUUGGUUCCAAUGCUGGGAUUGGCUGCUUUUCGUUGGAUUUGGUCUAGGGAGUCCCAGAAAGAAGUAGAAAAAGAGAGAGAAGCCUACCGUCGGAGAACUGCUGCUUUUCAACAGGAUCUGGAAGCCAAGUACCACGCCAUGAUCUCAGAAAAUCGGCGUGCUGUCGCUCAGUUGUCCUUGGAACUCGAAAAGGAACAAAACAGAACUGCUAGUUACCGAGAAGCCCUUAUCUCUCAGGGACGCAAGUUGGUAGAAGAAAAGAAGCUUCUGGAACAGGAACGGGCCCAGGUGAUGCAAGAAAAAAGACAGGUGCAGCCUUUGAGAAGUGCGUAUUUGAGCUGCCUGCAAAGGGAAGAAAACUGGCAAAGGAGAGCCAGGCUUUUGCUGAAAGAAUUUGAAGCUGUUCUCACAGAAAGACAGAAUAUCUACUGCAGUCUGUUUCUUCCUCGCAGCAAGCGGCUGGAGAUAGAGAAGAGCUUACUGGUGCGAGCGUCCGUCGACCCCGUCGCCGCUGACCUAGAGAUGGCAGCCGGUCUCACCGACAUAUUUCAGCAUGAUACAUACUGUGGUGAUGUCUGGAACACCAACAAACGCCAGAAUGGCAGACUCAUGUGGCUCUAUCUCAAAUACUGGGAACUCGUUGUCGAACUGAAGAAGUUUAAGAGAGUAGAGGAAGCCAUACUAGAAAAGUAAGACAAGAGUGAAAUCAAACUGCUUUUAGUGACUCGAGGCCAGGCAGUCAUGCGCCUUCUGGGUCUCCGGCGUCUUCCGUUCCCGUGCUGCCCGUGUCAUGGCCACACCGUCACCCUUCAGCAGCGACCUCCACUCCCGCCACCGUCUGAGCAGAAGUGCACCGAAGCCUCAGAGACAGAGGGUCUCCUCCCGAUGCUCUGCCGCUGUUGGGGAUAUGGUUUCUUGAAGCAUUUUUAGGCUGCCAGUAUUGUAUUAAGCAGAACAGUAUAACCUCGUAUUUUAGCUCCAGGGUAAAAAUGGUUUUUUAAAAAGUCAAAUACAAUACUGGUCCUUACCACAAGUAAUUUUCUGUCUGUUUCAUCACUCCCUAAAUACUUUCUCCUCAAAUUAUUUUUCUCUGUCACCAGAUUACAUUAAGAAUUUGUCAGAUAAUGUGUAGAACUGCAUAACAGGUAAUAGGAAGUAGUAAUAUUAUAUUAUCAAGGGUUUAUAUUUUAAAGAUCUCUCUCACUCCAUAAAGGGGAAAUACCAAGUGUUUCUUGUAUCCAGUUGUUACUUAAUGUGUGUUUGUUGUAUGCAGUUGUUACCUAAUGUGUGUUUGUUGUAUGCAGUUGUUACCUAAUGUGUGUGUGUUGUAUGCAGUUGUUACCUAAUGUGUGUGUGUUGUAUCCAGUUGUUACCUAAUGUGUGUUUGGAAUUUGGCUUGUGUCUGUAUUCAGCAAGCAGAUACUUAUUAGCAAUGAUAUAUACUCAAAAUACUUGCCAUUUAUGAGUAAUAAUGCCACUUUUUGUGUAAUUCUUCACUCUUUACAAAAUAUUUUUAUAUGUAUUAUCUCAUUGUUUACCACAGCCAACAAGGUAGACAGGCACUUAUCACCCCAUGUCACACAUAGCUACUGGGAAUUGAGCCUGUAUACCUGUUCACUCAUGGAAUCCUCAGUCGAAUCCUGUGAAGUGAGUAUUACUAUUACGCUUUGCGGAGGUGCCCCAAGGCCAGCCCCCAGGUGCGUGACCUGCUGGGAGAUCUCACAGGACUCAGCACAGGGUUGGACUCAGCACAGAGCAGAAUCAGCAAAGGGAGAGGGUGUGUGGGUGGCGCUCAGAGGAGCCACGUGUGGACACCCCAGGAUCCACUCCCUGGAGUCAUACAGGACACACCUAACUAUUAAGAAUAAGCUCACUGGAGACUCAGCACCUGGGGCUUUUGCUAAGGGCUGGUCAUGUGGUACCCCCUGCCUGGCCUGUGUGGGAAUUCCCCACUUGUCCAGAAGGAGGGUGGGUUUGGUGUGGUCUGUGCCGUGAGCACAAGUACUGUGGUCACAGAGCCACGCGUAGGAGUUAAUGGUGCUGGGAAGUCUCCCAGAAUCCGAGUUCCCAGAUGUCAGUCAAGGGCCAGCCUUGCACACAGGCCCUGGUAGGACACAGCCUUGGGCCUGCUGUGUGAAUUCGUCACCACGCACCUCACUUUACGGAGAUGUGGAAGAGCUAACCUGCCUGAGGUCACGCAGGUAGUAGUGUUGGAGCCAGUCUGAGCCCGGGCACCUUUUCUCCAGAACCGCGAGUAACCUGUGUGCAGUGAUUUGAUAGUGUGUGGCCAGGCAGGAGCGGGAGCAGGUUGUCCAUCUGCUUUCAAGGGCCAUGUUCUCCCCUCCUGCCCGUCUGUACGGGAGUAGGAGCAACUGUUAAAAAUCCUAAGCUCAUAGAGCCCACGUGGCAGUAUGAGAGCCACUAUUCAUGGAGUGCAUGUUCCACCCUGAGCUGUACACGCUUUACACGCAUGCGUUGUUUGAAAUCCGUGGAACCCCUUGAGCGCGGCGGAGGCGGGCUCAGAGCCAACAUGCGCUGCCUGCAACAGACACGGGCCCCCUGCCAUGCUCUGCUCUCGGCACCCACGCCCUGCUAAGGGUGCUCAGAUGCUUCACCCAGGCAGGAGUGCAGUGGUGUGAUGGCUAAGGGUGCUCAGAUGCUUCUCUUCUUCAGUGGCUGCUAGCGUGCCUCUCUGCUCUACCACCAUCGCUUUAUCUGAGAAAAAGUCACUUUUAUUUUCAUUUUUUAUUUUUUUUGAGAGGGAAUCUCUGUCACCCAGGCAGGAGUGCAGUGGUGUGAUCUCAGCUCACUACAGCCUCCGCCUCCUGGGUUCAAGCGAUUCUCCUGCCUCAGCCUCCUGGGUAGCUGGGAUUACAGGCGUGCGCUACCACACCCAGCUAAUUUUUGUUUUGUUAGUAGAGACGGGGUUUCACCAUGUUGGCCAGGCUGGUCUCGAACUGCUGACCUCAGGUGAUCCACCGCCCCCACCUCGGCCUCCCACAGCACUGGGAUUACAGGUGUGGGCCACGGCACCCGGCCCCUAAAAAGUCAUUUUUUCGGUAAAUCUGGACAAAACUCUUCCUGUUGUUGUUUGUACUUCCUGAUGCAUCAAGACCCUUGCCUAAAGAGCGGUGCAGGCUCCAUUCCUGCGGCAAUCCGGUCUGCUGGGUGUCCCUGUGUGAACCACUCCACGUUUGUCUUUAAAUGAAGAAAACACAGUCAGCUGCUUUGUAGGUGAAUGAUUUUCGAGGCAAAUUGUUAAUCCUCAUCCUGUUUCUAAUGUCCAGUGUGCUGUCAGCCUAGCUUCCUUCUAUAGUGAGAUAGAUAUGUUCAGAGCCUUCAAGCUGGUGUGGACACUGACCCGCUGACCCGGUCCUGCAGAGUUAGGAAGACGAGCAUUUUUUUUUUGAGACAGUCUCGUUCUGUUGCCAGGCGGGAGUGCAGUGGCACAAUCUCGCCUCACUGCAAGCUCUGCCUCCCGGGUUCGAGUAGUUUGCCUGCCUCAGCCUCCCGAGUAGCUGGGACUACAGGUGCCUGCCACCAUGCCUGGCUAAUUUUUGUAUGUUUAGUAGAGACAGGGUUUCACCAUGUUGGCCAGGAUGGCCUCAAACUUCUGAUCUCAGGUGAUCCACCUGCCUCAGCCUCCCAAAGUGCUGGGAUUAGGGGCGUGAGCCACCGUGCCUGGCCGGAAGAUGCUCUUUCCACAGGGUUGAUAUUAGUUCGUGUUUGUGUGGCGUGGCUGCCUUCCAUCAGCAAGUUUGAGUGUUGAUGUGAGGCCACCCUCUUUUGAAAUGGAUUGUGGUCGGUUUGGAAUAGUUACACGGUGCUGUGCCAUUUGGUAACUCCACACAUGUACCGAAAGGUGAGCCCACAGUGGAACGCUCCUCAACCAAAGUGGUUUAAAGUUGCAGAAAAGGGUAAUUGUGCUGGUUGGUGUGUGUGCUGAAUUUGUAGCGACAUCAGAGUCAAGCAUUAUUUGUCCUGCUGCUUUCUUGGAGGUCACAGUAACUAUAAAACCGUGAGCCAGCAAGGCAGAGAGGACCCUUUGGGGUAAGGAGUGGAGCUCUGGGAGAUCCUAGGUUUCGGAAGCAGGUCCAGUUUCCUUGGGGAGGGGAGGGCUCGCUGCAGGGCGGAGGAGGGGCAGCCACUGUAAUCCUUGUCUGGAGUGAACAUUGUAUAUGAGGUUGCAGUGGCUUAAAAAGGAAGGACUUUUGCGGGGAGGGGUUGAGAUUGUACUUUCUAAUUUCGCUUGCUUCAGACUUGACUUUGGAAUGAAGUUCGAAGGCAUCACAAUUGACCUGGACAUUCCAAAAACAAAACUGAAGAGGCAGCAUUUCUCUUCCGUAGUCCAGUCAGCUCAUUUGGUAGAUGCGCUUUUUCCUCCUUUGCGCUUAUUCAUCCAUAAGGAUAUAUAAUUUGCAUAUAUAUUUCAUAUGCGUGCAUAUGUGUGUGUAUGUGUGAACUGGCAGGUGUUGAUUUCAUAAGGACAAAAUUGUUCUGCAAACCUUGCACCAAUUAUGGGGUGUUUCAACGGAAAAACUUCACCAAAUGAUCUGUGUGUUCUUUCAAAGAGAAGUUAUGUCUAAUUAAAAUGUGUAACGGACUAUUUCUGUGUUGGAUUGUUUAAAAAGUGAUUGCUUCAUAGUGUACUAAGAUCAUCUCUUUAAGCAGAAGGGAGAAAACAGCUUUCUAGUUACUUUCACAUAUUAGGUUUGCUACAUAAAAGCAAGUCUGAAGACUACACCUGUGACAUUGCAGAGACCAAACUGCAGUGUGUGCAGCCAUGAGUGGCAGCUGCUUCCUCCUCGAGGUGUCUUGUUCCAGCAUGAGGACAGCCCGUGCGAUGUUGGGAGGAGCCAGGGUGUUUGGGGGGGCAGCUGCCCUAGACACUGGCUGGCUGUGAUGGGGGGCAGCCUGCUGUGUAGACACUGGCUGGCUGUGAUGGGGGGCAGCCUGCUGUGUAGACACUGGCUGGCUGUGAUGGGGGCAGCCUGCUGUGUAGACGCUGGCUGUGAUGGGGGCAGCCUGCUGUGUAGACGCUGGCUGGCUGUGAUGGGGGCAGCCUGCUGUGUAGACGCUGGCUAGCUGUGAUGGGGGCAGCCUGCUGUGUAGACGCUGGCUGGCUGUGAUGGGGGCAGCCUGCUGUGUAGAAAGUGCUGGGCUUGCUCCGUCUGCCUUGACUUGUGUGAGUAACUGCGCUGGGUUUUAUAGGUUGAGGCUGAAAAGGCUCCUCUUUCUAUGCUGGGUUUGACGAAACAGUUGCUGUAUUUCUCUAUUAAUUUAGGAUUCUGUUUGCAAGCAGCAGAGAUGGAUUUGUGCUAGCCUAGAAAGUUAAAGAGGGAUUUAAGGCUGUCUCGUGAAACUUCAGGUCAAGAAUGGAGAACACAGGUUAGAUGUCAGAGAAGAACCAGAAAGACAAAUAAGGGACUCUCAGGGGCCUCGGAGUACUUGUCACUCUGUGUCAUAUCUCUGCAUAGCCGCGCCAAUCCCCAAACCAGCUUCUCUGGCCACACGGUGGGACAGGGCGGUUCCCACAGCUCCUGAGCCUGCCCCCUGCCUGGCCUGCUCCAGCGGGCGGCCGAGUUAGGGAAGCGCUGGGCUCCACCAUACCGCGGUGUUCUAAAGGAGUGGGAACAAUGAAGAUCAGGGUUGCAGAGCCUGUGGCCUUUGCUAGCUUCAUGGGAAAUCUUGAAAAGAGAAAACGAAGGGCUUCAGUAAGCCACCCAUGGACAGCAGGCAUGCGGUGGAAGGCGGAGGGCUUCUGUGGCAGCUUCGCAGGUCUCUCAUCUGCUGCAGACCCCCUGACAGGCUGAGGGUCUUGCUGUCGGGUAGCGGGACCAGAUGAGCCUGAAUGUGGCUCUGCGGCUCACAGGACAAGUGUACCUUGAGAGCUGCUGCCGCCGCCUGGAUGUUUGCUGGGUGAGCUCCAGAUUCACGGGAGCCCUUUGUGCCAGCAUGGCCGCCCCAACCCCAUGGGGAAAGCAGAUCUCCCUCACCUGGGAAUCUGGCAGAGACCUCAGGCAGUGCCCCAUCUUUCAUGACCUGCCUGGUCCAGGUAGAGGAGUCAAGUCCUGCUCCAGGAGCAGGUGCAGGGCCUGGCCUGGGUGCCGAGAGUGGGGUGAGGAGGGAGGAGUAACGAAGAAAGGCAGAUGGGCAGAAAGUGCCACAUUGGGGCACUCAAGUGGCUCUGUUUAAUAUUCCAGCAGGGACACUGAGACCGAGCCCAUCCCUGCUGGGAGAGCUUCUCGAAGCUGGUUGGUGGCUGACAGGCAGGGAGUGGGGUGCUGGGGCCUCCUCGGGAGGUAGGGGUGCUGGGGCCCUGCUCUUGACAGCACUGUGCCAUAGCUCCGAGGUGGCUGCUCCCCAUGGGCCAGGGCUGGUGGUGCCAGAAAAUGGGAUCUGGGCUGAGGGGCUCUGGGCUGGCAGAGGUGGGGCGGGGGGUGACUGGCAGGCAUCAAGAUGGGGGGGGACAAGCACGGUGCCCCCACCCAUGGGGCCGUGUGGGGCUGAUGGAUAGUGGGACUCCAGCAUGCAGCAGAUGAUGGAGCCUUGCUCAACUCAGAAGAGGAAGAGCAGGAGAGCGCUGGUGGAUGAGAGCAACCCUGAUGUUCCAGGGCCCUUGGCCACGUCCACCACACAGAGGGGCCACGUCCACACAGAGGGGCCACGUCCACCACACAGAGGGGCCACGUCCACCACACAGGGGCCACUGGGCCUGCGUAUAUCUCCUUGGCCUGCGAGGGUAUCAUCAUUUCCUGACCUGUGGAACAAGUCAUUAAGCCAGGAAGGACUUGAGUUGGAGCCCCUAAAACGGCCCCCACUCCUUGCCAGGAUGGUGGACAGGAAGCAGUGCCAUGUUCUGAAGGAGCUGCACCAGCCCAUGCUGCUGUGGAAGACCCAAGGGAGGCAAAGACGGUGGCUCCAGAUGGCGGCCCCCAUUGGGACCCUGCUCACAUCACCCACUGGCCCUGGAAAGCCGGGGUGGGCCUGGGCAGGUGAACCCUGAGGCUCCGCCAGGAGCAGCCCCAGCUACAGCCACCAUGGAUGUUUGCUGGGUUGGAUCAGCACUCUCACCUGCUGAAUGGUUUUGCCUGAUUCCCACUAGCUUGUCUUGUGUGGGAGGCCGUGUUUUCUGCGGUAGAGAAGUGCUCUCCAUAAAAACCCAGCAGGCGUGCUCCUGGGCCCUGCAGACGCCGGAUGUGUGGCCACAGACGCCAUGCGACCCAGGACUGGAGUCACAAGAUUGGGCGAGGACAAAGACCCAGCGAAUGGUGAACGGCCAUGCAGGAUGGGGCCGAUCAGUUCAGUAGGAGCAAGUGCGAGACCUGCACAGGACGGGCGAGGGAGGCGUUGGUCCCCAGCCUCUGCUGGCCUUAUCAGAAUGGGCUGUUCUUGGGAAGCCCCUGGGUGUCUGUGGAGCUGGAGAUGUUGGGAGCUUGUGCCCUCAGCACCGCCCACUGACACCAGUGGGCUCCUGUGUGCCCUGCCCAAUCCCAGGCCUCAGGACACCCAGCACCCUGGGCCCUUCUCCACUGCCACAGGCCUUAAGGUUGGUCAUCAUGCCGCCCAGCGGCUGAGUCUUACAAUAAAAAUUCAGACACAAAGCAGUGGCAGCCACUCUGUGCUUUAGAGUUAGAAGUAAGUCAUUAAAAAUGUUGGCCCAGCACCUUCCCUGCCUGUUUCCAAAAGCUGGCCGCAAUAUCAAAUUCAUGUCCCUGGACAAGGCUCCAGUAAGGCACUGCCUGCAGUGUGCAGAGAGCACUUAGGUGGUUGCAGAGCAGGCAGAGACGAAUGUGGGGAGUGGAAGUCACCAUAUCUGCCCACUCGGCAGGAGGCCGUCCAUUCCUGAGACGCCCCCGGGAGGCAGGCUCCUGUACGGCACUCAUGCUGGGUACCCAACCCCUACAACCCAGGCAAACCCCUACCCUGGGCAGAGAAGGGCCUGGACACACCAGGGGCAGAAGGAGAAAGGGGAUGGAGACAAACCUGGGUGGGGGUGACCUGGGGGCAGCUGGGGUGGGGUGACACGGGGACCAUUGGGGUGGGGACACACUCCGGGAGGGGGAGACACGGGGCAGCAGGGGUGGGGGCACACCUGGAGUGGGGUGACAUGGGGGCCCCUGGGGUGGGGACACACUCGGGGAGGGGGUGACACAGGGACCACUGGGGUGGGGACACACUCCGGGAGGGGGUGAUACGGGGCAGCGGUGUAGGGAAAAGAGAGAUCAGACUGUCACUGUGUCUAUGUAGAAAGGGAAGACAUGAGACUCCGUUUUGAAAAAGACCUGUACUUUAAAUAAUUGCUUUGCUGAGAUGAUGUUAAUGUGUAGCUUUGCCCCAGCCACUUUGCCCCAACCUGGAGCUCACAAAAACAUGUGUUGUAUGAAAUCAAGGUUUAAGGGAUCUAGGGCUGUGCAGGACGUGCCUUGUUAACAAAAUGUUUACAAGCAGUAUGCUUGGUAAAAGUCAUCGCUAUUCUCUAGUCUCAAUAAACCAGAGGCACAAUGCACUGCGGAAAGCCGCAGGGACCUCUGCCCUUGAAAGCCGGGUAUUGUCCACGGUUUCUCCCCAUGUGAUAGUCUGAAAUAUGGCCUCGUGGAAUGAGAAAGACCUGACCGUCCCCCAGCCCGACACCCGUAAAGGGUCUGUGCUGACAUGGGUUAGUAAAAGACGAAAGCCUCUUGCAGUUGAGAGAGAGAAGUCCACUGUCUCCUGCUCGCCGCUGGGAACUGAAUGUCGCGGUGUAAAACCCGAUUGUACAUUUGUUCAACUCUGAGACAGGAGAAAAGCCGCCUUGUGGCGGGAGGCGAGACAUGUUUGCGGCAAUGCUGCCUUGUUAUUCUUUACUCUGCUGAGAUGUUUGGGUGGAGAGAAACAUAAAUCUGGCCUACGUGCACGUCCAGGCAUAGUACCUUCCCUUGAACUUAAUUACGACAUAGAUUCUUUUGCUCACACGUUUUUGCUGACCUCCUCCUUAUUAUCACCCUGCUCUCCUACUACAUUCCUUUUUGCUGAAAUAAUGAAAAUAAUAAUAAAAACUGAGGGAACUCAGAGGCCGGUGCCAGUGCAGGUCCUUGGUAUGCUGAGCGCCGGUCCCCUGGGCCCACUGUUGUUUCUCUAUA